AAAACUCACGCCCCAAACAAAACGCAAGGAGAGGAGGGCGCGCGGCCUGCAGCCCUCGCCCGCGUCCCCGGCCGCGGCGUGAUGCGCGCGGACCAGCCCGCGACGCCCGGGCUGCCGCUGUCCCCGCACCUGGACGCUGGCGCGGUGGCCGCGCCCCAGCCUCGAUCGCUCGCCGCGGCGACUCGGCCCCAGGCUUCCGGCGCCGGUGGGGGCCCUCGCUCUCCAUGGGGCUGAGGGACUGGCUGAGAACCGUGUGCUGCUGCUGCGGGUGCGAGUGCUUGGAGGAGCGCGCCCUGCCUGAGAAGGAGCCCCUCGUCAGUGAUAACAAUCCAUAUUCCUCAUUUGGAGCAACUCUGGUGAGGGAUGAUGAGAAGAAUUUAUGGAGUAUGCCCCAUGAUGUGUCCCACACAGAGGCAGACGACGACAGAACCCUGUACAAUUUGAUAGUCAUUCGUAAUCAGCAGGCCAAAGACUCAGAGGGAGUGCUCCAGAGUGGUGAGACAUCCAAGCUAAAGCAUAAAGCCAACCAUUGUUGGGAGUUAUUGACGGCCCCUCUAAGUCUUGAAGGUGCCAGACCGCUGGGCACAGGCCUCUCCUGGCCUCCACCCCCUGCCAACCGCUACUCCAAGGAGUGGCAGAAGCUCAACUAUGAUAUCCAUACCCUGCGGCAGGUUCGAAGGGAAGUAAGAAACAGAUGGAAGUGCAUCUUAGAAGAUUUAGGUUUUCAAAAGGAAGCUGACUCUUUGUUGUCAGUGACUAAACUCAGCACCAUCAGUGAUUCUAAAAACACAAGGAAAGCUCGAGAGAUGUUGUUAAAACUGGCUGAAGAAACCAAUAUUUUCCCAACAAGUUGGGAGCUCUCAGAGAGAUAUCUCUUUGUUGUGGACCGUCUCAUUGCACUUGAUGCUGCAGAAGAGUUCUUUAAGCUUGCUCGUCGAACUUACCCCAAGAAGCCUGGGGUUCCAUGCCUGGCAGAUGGCCAGAAAGAACUGCACUACCUUCCGUUUCCAAGUCCCUAAAGGAGAGGCUCAGGGGCAGAAUGGGAAUUCUUCCAUGAGGACUCAGCAGUCAACCAAAGUUGGACAAUUACAUGUAGAAGAGAGUGAGCAAAUAGAGUUUGCUUAGUGAAAAAUGAUACUGAAUUCUACAUAAAUGUAAAGUCUUUAAUCUGAGGACCCUGCCCCAUGAAUUGUGCAGGCUGCAUUGAAACGCCUUGGUGAUCUCAUAUUUAGGAAGAAAGUUAAAGAGUUGGUCAGAUGGAUAGUUCAUAAUGGGUGGUUCCAUUCUGAGAGCCCAUUGCCCCAGCUUUGGUUUUAGUUGUGUCAUAAUCUCUGAUCAUUAAUCCUACUGACUGAGUGGACUAUUUCAGUUAAUAAAACAAUAUGAUUAAUAGAGAGAGCUGUCAUUGAGUCCCAAAAUGGAUUGCCAGUUUUAAAAUAAUUAUUAUAAAAUGUAUGCUAACCCCAAAAUAAUACUAGGCAUGAGGUGACCUCUCUGAUUUGGUCACCUUGUAGAACCUUGGAGGGUGUCAGGGCAUCUCUUUGAGUAUCAGUUAUGAUUAUUCAGAAGUAUAGAUGUAUCAAAUGAUAGAAAUGACAAGGAAUGGCUGGGCGUGGUGGCUCAUGCCUGUAAUCCCAGCACUUUGGGAGGCCAAGGUGGGUGGAUCAUGAGGUCAGGAGUUCAAGACCAGCCUGACCAACAUGGUGAAACCCUGUCUCUACUAAAAAUACAAAAAUUAGCCAGGUGUGAUGGCACGCGCUUGUAAUCCCAGCUACCCAGGAGGCUGAGGUAGGAGAAUCGCUUGAGCCCGGGCAGUGGAGGUUACAGUGAGCCGAGAUUGCACCAUUGCACUCCAGCCUGGGCGACAGAGCGAGACUCCGUCUCAAAAAAAAAAAAAAAAAAAAAAAAAAAGAGUUAUGUAUUCAUGUGUUGUACUUGCAUUUUAAAUUCCCAACAUUAUUGAUAUCUGGUUCUCUCAUCUUUGUAUAUUGUCCAUUUCUAUUCCAAAAGCCUUUCGCUCUUUUUUUUUUUUUUUUUUUUUUUGAUGGACUCUCGCUCUGUCGCCCAGGCUGGAGUACAGUGGUGCGAUCUCGGCUCACUGCAACCUCCGCCUUCCGGUUUCAAGUGAUUCCCCUGCCUCAGCCUCUGGAGUAGCUGGAACUACAGGCGCGUGCCACCACACCUGGCUAAUUUUUUGUAUUUUUAGUAGAGACGGGGUUUCACCAUGUUAGCCACGAUGGUCUCGAUCUCCUGACCUCGUCAUCCGCCUGCCCCAGCCUCCCAAAGUGCUGGGAUUACAGGCGUGAGUCACCGCGCCCGGCCAAGCCCUUGGCAUUUUAUCUGGAAUAGCAUCUGUAAACUGAAGUGUUUGACCUCUGUUUUCUUCUCUCCUCUUUCAUCUGUUUCUGAUUCGUUGGCUGGCAGCUGCACCUGUGGGGGGACCUCUCAUGCAGACUUGCACAUAUGCAGGGAGUAUUGCACUGAAGAUCUUUGCUGGACCUUCUUCUCUUCAGAAGAUAAUUUUCAAAAGGGAGCAAUGCUGUGAAUGCAGCUUGCUUCUCUCUACAGAUUGAGAAGUCCAGCUUCAAAAGUUACUUGCCACUUAAGCAAGGAACUUGUCAAGAGAUCAUGGUUCAUGUUACUGAAAAGACUUUAAGGAUUUGUAAGGUUAAUCCAUAGAUUGCUGAGAAAAAUGGAAAUAUUUUUAUUUUUACAGAUUUUGCACUUCUGAAUUCAGGUUAAAAACUAACUUGUAUUUAGUCUGCUUAGAGGACUGUGACUUGAAAAUUUUUAUAUACCAAUGAGCUUUUUGGUAGCGUCCACAAUGUUUAAAAUAUUUCAUAGGCGAGAUCCGUGUUCUCCAUUUAUUAAUGCAUUGUAGACCAAUUUAACUGCUGUGUUUCAGGAAAAUUCUUCCUAGUUUAAUAAGCAAGCUAAAAGUUUUAUUUUUUAUAUUUAGUGCUUAAUCUUUGCCUCAUGUUAUGUAAAAUUAGCCUGCAGAUAUUUUCUCUCAAUUCUGUAGACUCUCGCAAGAUAAACAUUCAAACAGUGAAACAAACAAUAAAAUAAAUAAACCUAAGGAUGUCGUAUUGUUUUACUCUCGGUCUCAGAAUUUGUAUUUUGCCUUUCUGCCUUUUUUAUGUCAAAAUAGAUGAGAUUGUGUGCAUCUAUAAAUUGUUACCACAGUAUUUUUGAUAAUGAAUAAGGAUAGGACUAUCUCUGUGAUUAUUAAAAUACAUGGAAUUAUCCAGGAAAUUUUCCUUACAAGGAAUUAAAAGACUCCUGUAUUUACUUUUCA